GAGUCUAGUCUUUGUUCGGGGCUGUCCAAAGGACGCUAGCUGUUGCACCUGUUCCUCCCUGCGCGUAAGCUUCCUAUAAGACUGUUUUCUCUGAUUGACUUCUGGUGGCUUGGCUUCAUUAUGAUGUGUUUAUGUUCACAGAAAUUUUUGUAAUUUCUCUAUGGUAACAACUUUUUAUGCCUUAGGAGUGUCUCUGAGGCAGGAUUCUAAGAGAUUCUCUUUGACUCAAUCCCAGAUAGAGGAUAAAUCUCCUGGCAAAGCCCAGAAUGACCACAGCCCUGGAACCUGAGGACCAAAAAGGACUUCUGAUAAUUAAGGCAGAGGACCAUUACUGGGGACAGGAUUCCAGCUCACAAAAGUGCAGUCCUCACAGGAGGGAACUCUAUAGACAACACUUCAGGAAGCUCUGCUAUCAGGAUGCACCUGGACCCCGUGAAGCUCUUACCCAGCUGUGGGAGCUCUGCCGUCAGUGGCUGAGGCCAGAAUGCCACACCAAGGAGCAGAUUUUAGACCUGCUGGUGCUAGAACAGUUCCUGAGCAUUCUUCCUAAAGACCUGCAAGCAUGGGUGCGUGCACACCAUCCAGAGACUGGAGAGGAGGCAGUGACGGUACUGGAGGAUCUGGAGAGAGAGCUUGAUGAACCUGGAAAGCAGGUCCCAGGCAAUUCAGAAAGACGGGACAUACUCAUGGACAAGUUGGCCCCCUUGGGAAGGCCAUAUGAAUCACUGACUGUCCAGCUCCAUCCCAAAAAGACCCAGCUGGAGCAGGAAGCUGGGAAACCACAAAGGAAUGGCUGUUUGCUUCUCAAACAUAGAAUAGGACCCGUUUGUGUACUGUUUGUUUGUUACAGGUGAUAAAACUAGGACUAAGAAUGAAGAGUUGUUCCAGAAGGAAGAUAUGCCCAAAGACAAGGAAUUCCUUGGGGAGAUAAAUGACAGACUGAACAAAGAUACUCCUCAGCAUCCUAAGUCCAAAGAUAUUAUUGAAAAUGAGGGCAGAUCAGAAUGGCAACAGAGGGAAAGAAGACGAUAUAAAUGUGAUGAAUGUGGGAAAAGUUUCAGUCAUAGCUCAGACCUUAGUAAACACAGGAGAACUCACACGGGAGAGAAGCCCUAUAAAUGUGAUGAGUGUGGAAAAGCCUUCAUUCAGCGCUCACAUCUCAUUGGACAUCAUAGAGUACACACGGGAGUAAAACCCUAUAAAUGUAAAGAAUGUGGGAAAGACUUCAGUGGGCGCACAGGUCUUAUUCAGCAUCAGAGAAUCCACACAGGUGAAAAACCCUAUGAAUGUGAUGAGUGUGGAAGGCCUUUCCGAGUAAGUUCAGCUCUUAUUAGACAUCAAAGAAUUCAUACCGCAAAUAAACUCUACUAAUAUAGCAGUAAUAUCAAAAGUUCUUUGGACACUCAGGCCUAACUAGUUAUCAAAGAAUCUAUUUUAGAAACCUUGAGUUUCCUCAAUGUGGUCAAAGCUUCAGUCAUCAUUAAACUUCUCUGGACCAAAGAA